CUUAAGGUUAGGAUAUGUGGAGUUUGUGGAUAUUAUUAGACCUGAAAAUCCACCUAAAUGAAUUCCUUUCUAUCACAACUAAGGGAAUUUACGUCUACAUUUAAUUUGUGACUGUUUUUGCUUUUUAAUUUAUCCAGUAUGAAGCCUGCUUAAGCACAGACUAUUUUGUGUCUGUGGAUAUCAGACCUGAAAAUUUGUCUAAAUGAAUCAUUCUUUCUUUUCUUUCACAGCUAAGCCAGAUAAUUUGUGCUUGCAUAUAAUUUGUGACUGUUUUUGCUUUCUUUUAAAUUUAUCCAGUAUUAAUUGCUUAUCUCUGCCCUCUUCAUUACAUUGGGUUCUCUGAACUGUGUGCGUGUUCAUCUCCAAAUUUCCCCUUUUUAUAAGGACAACAGUCAGAUUAGGUCCCACUCUAAUGACCUCAUUUUAACUUGAGUGUCUCACUGAUGACCCUGUCUCCAAUAAGGUCACAUUCUGAGGUACUGGGCAUUAGGACUUCAACAUUUGAAUUUGGAGGGGACACAACCCAUAAUAGUGGUGUUUCCAGAAGCAGGUGGAUAGGGAAGGCAAAUUCAUACUUAGAGCAGGUUAUCUGUUACUAUAUCUUUCAUGAUGAAUCGUGAAGGUGUAAUCAUCCUGCCACCAGACAGUUGACUGAAUCUCCCAAGGAAUGGUGCUAUAAUGGGAACUCGUUGGCCUCUGUUCCUUGCAGGUUGAGCACUGACCGUAACAAUAGCCAGAUUAAUCUUGGUGUAGAAAGUCUUACCUUGUUGACUUGCAUGCACAGACUCAAGCCCAGUUGCCAUGGCCAUUUGUAAAUGGGCCUAUUGAGCAGGCAUUCAAGUGGCUGUGGACUUAACUGGUGUUCACAAAAUGGAUGAUCUUGUAUACCUGAUCUUUAAAAAUUUUCUCUGCCACGUGUGCACCCUUGGCUGAACAUUCACACAAACACCGUUAUCCUUCUAUUCUAUUCUCAGGAUAACUUCUUUUUUUUUGUUUUGUUUUGCUUUUUGAGACAGAGUCUUACUCUGUCCCAGGCUGGAGUACAGUGGUGUGAUCUUGGCUCACUGCAACCUCCACUUCCCUGGUUCAAGCAAUUCUCGCACCUCAGCCUCCGGAGUAUCUGGGAUUACGGGAGUGCAGCACCACGCCCAGCUGUUUUUUUGUUUUUUUUUUAAUUUUUUGUAGAGAUGGAGUUACACCAUGUUGGCCAGGCUGGUCUCGAACUCCUGACCUCAAGUGAUCCACCCACCUCGGCUUCCCAAAGUGCUGAGAUUACAGGCGUGAGCCACCACGCCCGGCUGUAUUUUCAGAAUAACUUAUAUUCUGAGAUGUUCAGCAAUGUACCUCUUCCCCAGACUUCCUGGUCACCAGUUUUUUAAGUCUUCUUUUUAGCCUCUGUUCCUGAUACAUUGCUGAUCUCUACCUCUGGCCAUCUCUUGGUACACAAAAUGGGCAACAAGAUGUACUGCCCAAAGUUGUACACAGGGCUACUCUCUGAGUUGGGUUUAUAUUAUAGCAGUUGUUCACUUGGCUGGUUCUAAAAUUAUGCAAAUCCUUUGUAAAGUCAAGCUGGUUCAGGCUGGGUGCAUUAGCUUAUGCCUAUAAUCCCAGCAUCUUGGGAGGCUGAGGCAGGAGGAUUGCUUGAGCCCAGGAGUUCAAGACCAGCCUGAGCAAUAUAGUGGGACUCCUGUCUCUGCAAAAAAAAAAAAAAAAAUUUUUUUAAUUAGCUGGGCAUGCUUACAUGCAGCUGUAAUCUCAGCUACCCGGAGGCUAAGGAGGGAGGAUUACUUGAGCCCAGAAGGUUGAGGCUUCAGUGAGCCAUAAUUAUGCCACUGCACUCCAGCCUGGGUGACACAGUGAGACCUGUCUCACAACAUACAAAUGAAGUUUAAGGAUUUCUUCCCUCUUUAUCAGGUCAUAAAGAAUUUUCUCUUUUCUUUCUUUUCGAGACAGAGUCUCAUCCUGUCGCCCAGGCAUGAUCUCGGCUCACUGAAACCUCUGCCUCCCGGGUUCAAGUGAUUCUCCUGUCAGCCUCCCACGUAGCUGGGAUUACAGGCGUGUGCCACCAUGCUCAGUUAAUUUUUGUGUUUCACCAUAUUAGCCGGGCUGAUCUCAAACUCCUGACCUCAGGUGAUCCGCCUGCUUUGGCCUCUCCAAGUGCUGGGAUUACAGGCGGCAGCCACUGUGCCCAACCUAUCAGGUCAUAAAGAAUUUUUUAUAAUGCCUCAGGUAAUAGUUGAAGAAGGGGCAGCAGUGAUGCAGAAGCAGGUACCAUGAGAGUCUGAGACAUCUGCACAUGCAAUUUAUUUGUGUCUCUUGAACCUACUCAAGUCCAUUCUCAAGUAUACCAUUUCUACUUGAUGAUGGGUUGCUGCUGCCAAUGCUCCGUUUUAGGCUAGGUAAAUCAGAUACCCAGAUCACAUAACGGCUCAAGUCUCAUGGUCAUUUGAUGUUCUGUGGUCAACCAUUCUGCUUUUAUCAGGAUUUAUUGUCAAGUCAAUAGCUGUUUCACAAAAAUACAUCAGUCAGUUCUGUUUUUAAAAUGUGAAUUUAUUCCAGUGUUAAUACAUUAGAGAACGAUUUGAGCAUAAUCCAAAAUUUGCAUGUGCUUAUGUGCAGUUUUGUCCAUGAGAAAUAGUAGGUGAUCAUAGAAAAUUGCUUCCAGCUGAACCAAGCCACAUAAAACACACACGUUUCCAGUAUCCACUGGCUGCCUCUUUUUACCAUGUAUAUUAUCCUGUUAGGUGGUGAUAUGCUAUUCUUUGACAUUUGUGAUCUUUUCUAUUUGAAAAAAGCACUCAUUCAACAUCUCAAACCUACCUAAGCAUUCUGGUUCAAAAAUGCCACACAGUACAUGCAGAGGGAAUGUUUUGAGUAUUAAGGAGAAGCUUGAAACAAGAAAACAUUUGGAAAGAUAAAAACAUAACGAUACAUCCCAAGCAACAGAUAUAAAGGAAUCCACAUUAUGGACCAUCAAAGAUAAUGCCACAAAAAUAAAAGUGUAUGUAUGGCUGGACCAGGUUCGAGUGCUGGAAAGUCCAUAAGAACAAGGCAUAAAGAAACAGAAGAAAAAGAAAGAUUGUCAAAUAUUUGGAUUCAAGACCAAAGGGUGAAAAACUUAAGGAACAACCUUUCUCAUACAGAUCUUUGUAAUUAUAUACACAGACCUAAAAUAGAAGUCACUGUACCCUGCAUAAGUGGCUCCUUUUAGUGCUAGUAGUGGUUGCUUUAAUGAUUUCAAACAGUGCUACAGUUUCCUACAAACAAUGCUACAGUUUCCUAAGCCUUUGGCUGUCAGACAUAACUAUUAGUGUAGAUAUGAAAGCUGCAAAAGAAUUUUUCAGCAGUGAUAGGGAAGUAAAUUGAAGGCAGCUGUGCAUGGUGUUAAAUUCUUGGUUUUGAUUAAACAAAUAUCUGUUAUGAACGCAUGCCUCGAAUAACCCAAAUAUGAAAGACAGAAAACAUGUUCUAGGAUUUAAGGCUCCUAAAGGUAACAUAACUGUGAUAUUUGGCACCAGUGCCAAAUGGAGAUUUGAAGCUGAAGCCAAUAAUGUCACUCACCAAACUUUGAGCCUUUUAAAAGAUAUUGUUAACGUCAGCCUUUGAGGUUCAUGUCAGGUAUAGCAAAAAUGUAUGGAUGGCUGCCCACAUUUGCAUUUAUAUUUUUACUUAGUUCUUCUCUGUUAAAGAGGAUGAAUGCCCCAAAACAUUAAAAAAAAAAAAAAACUUAACUUUAAAAAUUCUUACAGUGUAUCAAGCUCUCUCUCUACAAAAGCAGAAUUCAACCUAUGUCACAUUCUUCCUUUUGCCUCCAAAAACCACCUCUCUGAUAACAGCCCCUUUUUAAGUGUGUGACAGCAGUGUUUAUAGCUUACUAUUUAAAGUGAACAUUUUAGAUAUUAAUUGCUGUUAUCUAAGGCAGGGUUGCAGAAGUGGUUACAGAAUGUUGGAAGAGGUUUAACAUUGCAAUGUCAUUGUUGAAGCCUGGAGUAAUAUACCGAGAGUGUUUGUGUUAUGUGUGGCAGAAAAUUGCCUUUGACUUGAUUCUUUAUUUUGAAGAAUUUGAUACUUCAGAGAAAUUUUAAAAGUUUAAAACAAGCUAUAUUGAUCUAAGAAAAACAGUUUGGACUCGGAGCAGUCAAAAAUGAGGAUAUUGAGAAGUUUCUAGGGUCCUGUCCUGAUGAUCUAACCACAGAAAACAUUCAGCAACUUGCUGCUUAUGGCUGUAUGGAUGCAGAAGAUGUCGAUGACAGUGAUAAUGAAAGUCAGAAGUCUGUGUAUGCCAUGACAGUGUAAUACAAAUGAUCAGAUGUUUUAAAUGCUGUGAAAAUAAUUGGACUGCCUUGAAGAUAAUGGCUUUACUGCUGAAGAUAUUAGGAUAGUCUUGUGUGGCAUCCGGAUGAAUUUGGAACCGUACAGGCAGCUUUAGUGUAAAAGGAGGAGGCUGGCAACACCACAGAAAUUUUAUUUAUUCUUUAUAUUUUAAGUUAGUACAGCAGACAUAACACAAGGACAGUGAGCUACAACCUUCUGUAUCUGGUGUUAAAAAUUUCCAUUCAUUUUCAGAUAACCUGUUUUUUGCCACUUUACAAUAACUCGUAAGCUGUAACUCUUCCAAUGUCCACAAGCAAACUUCAGCUCAUAUUUAUUGUAGUAUUUAGGUAUUAACUAUUUAAUGUGUGUAAAAUUGUAUCAUUUUUAUUAGAUUGCCUUCUCUUUUUAUAUGUCACUGAUGAAGUUUUUGACAUUGUAUCUCUAACAGUUUUUCUCCUAAAGGCUGCAAUUUUUAACAAUUUUGCAUAAUGCAGUAAUUUUUGGAAAUAUAUGUGUCACAGCAAAACUGACUGUGGUCAGUAGAAGAGGACAUGAUGACCUUUCUUUAAAACUCUCUAAAACGAUUUUCCCACUGGGGCUUGCCAAAGACUUCAUACAACAUCCUUACCUGCAACAGAUUCUUGGAGAAUCAUUGCAUCUGCUGGUCACGAAACCCAAGUGGCGGAGUACCUUGUAUUGCACUCUGGACCUGGUACAGAGCCGUCUCUUAACCUGGGCCCCAUUCAUAACUGACAUUCUUUUUUUUUUUUUUUUCUUUUGAGAUGGAGUCUCGCACUGUUGUCUGGGCUGGAGUGCAAUGGCAUGAUCCUGGCUCACCGCAACCUCCGCCUCCCGGGUUCAAGCAAUUCUCCCACCUCAGCCUCCCGAGUAGCUGGGAUUACAGGUGCCUGCCACCACGCCUGGCUAAUUUUUUGUAUUUUUAGUAGAAACGGUGUUUCACUGUGUUGGCCAGGCUGGUCUCAAACUCCUGACCUCGUGAUCCACCCGCCUCAGCCUCCCAGAGUGCUGGGAUUACAAGCGUGAGCCAGCGUGCCCAGCCAUAACUGACAAUCUUAAGAGGUAUUUUAUAAAAUGAAUCAAGCAGUACACACCCUAAUGAAGUAUAUCUUGCCUCCAGUGUGCAGUGAGCUCCCAAUGUCCAGUCUAAAGAGGCAGAUAGGUGCGGCCUUUCUUUUUUCUUAAGAGUGGAGUUUGCAACAUGCUCCAGACUACACUCCCACGAAAGUGGUGGGCCUCAGAGUGAGGAUGGUUAUUCCUUCACCCUGAUAUGUGGCAUGUACGUAUCUGACCAGUACCAUUGAAAAUACCCACUACCUGUAUCAAGUCCAGUCAACAUGAUGUCAGUAUAGUGGAUCAAGUGAUACUCUCUAGACUGUGCAAAACCAUCUAAGUCCAUGAGUACUGUAUUAUUUGAGAGAGCCAGGAAAGUUACUCUAACUCUGAAGACUGAAGGUAUAUCAUUAAACCUGCCAAGAUAAAAACGGAUUGUUUCUGUUUGAUCUAAUUGGGAAAGGGGAAAAAGCAAGUACUUGAUUGAUAACUGCAUAGCCAUAUUGAUUUGCUCCAGCAAAAAUACCACAUCCUGUAAAGCAGCUGCAGCUGGAGUUUGAUUGUUUAUGAUACUCUUAAAUACUUGCAAGACUCAUCUACUUUUUGUAUAGGUCAAGGAGGCAUCUUACAUUGGGAUGGGAUGGUGGUGUCAAUAUCUGCAGUUCCUUUAGGACUGUAGUAAUUGCUUAUUGUUUUGAUUGAGAGGGACAAUUCUAGGGACUUGGAUUUGGUGUUUCCUAUAAUAGUAGCCCAUACAUCAUGGGUCAGGGAACUGAUAUAGUAUGGGAUUUCUGCCAGUGCCAAAUAUGUCUGUUCCAACUAUGAUUCUGGAGAUGGAAAAAUAAGCACUGGGUCGAAUCAUAUCCCUUGGGCCCGCUGAGACAGAUACAGUCCCAAAUUUUAUCAGCUAGCUUUUGUAAAGUGUCUGUGUAACCUCCUGGACCACAUGAGUAUAUUCAGUCACCAGGGAUAAGCAGAGCUGGCAUAAGUGUGGGACCCAAGAGCAAACAACACAUGAUAGGCACACCAUCUACUAAAUAUUUGAUUCCGAAGAGCUGUUUACUGUUUUCCAGAUAUUUUAUGUAUUUUUUUAUUGAGGUGAAAUUCACAUAGCAUAAAAUUAACCAUUUUAGAGUGAACUAUUUAAUGCUAUUUAGUACAUUCACAGUGUUGUAUACCAUCAUUCCUGUCUAGUUCCAAACGCUGUCAUCACCUCGUAAUAGCAUGCUAUACCCAUUAAGCAGUUUCUCCCCAUUCCCUCCUCCCCCUAACCCCUGGCAACCGCCAAUCUGCCUUCAGUCUCUGGAUUUACCUAUUCUGAACAUUUCAUUUAGGUGGAAUUAUAUAAUAUGUAACCUUUUAUGUCUAGCCUCUUAUUUUUUAAUUUCAGAAAAAUGUGUUUUAUUUGUUUUUUCUUUUUUCAACUUUAUGUUAGAAUUGGGGUACAUGUGCAAGUUUGUUACAAACGUAUAUUGCGUGAUGCUGAAGUUUGAAGUAUGAAUGAAUCUGUCACCCAGAUAGUAAGGAUAGUACUCCAUAGGUAGUUUUCCUUAACUCUUCCCCCACAUCCUCCCUCCGCCUUCUUGUGUUCCCCAGUGUCUGUUGUUCUCAUUUUUAUGAACACGUGUACCCAAUGUUUAGCUCCCAUUUAUAAGUGGGAAAUGUGGUAUUUGAUUUUUCUGAUUCCACAUUAGCUUGCUUAGGAAAUGGUUUCCAGCUACAUCUGUGUUGCUGCGAAGAACAUGAUUUUGUUCUUUUUUAUUAGCCUCUUACAUAGCAUAAUGCUUUCAGAUAUACUACAAUGUUCAUUCAUGUUGUGGUGUGUAUCAGUACUUCAUUCUUUUUUAUGACUUAGUGAUAUUCCAUUUUAUGUGUUUACCACAAUUUGUCCAUGACGCACAUUUGAUAUAUUAACAAAUGAACAACUGAAGUUUAGUUUUCACUUAUGUAGUGAAAAAGCAGUGGUCUAGAGUUAGAUACUUGGAUCUGUUCCCUCCUCAGCUGGUUGUUGUCCAUCUGUGAGCUUUAAAAUACUGUUCUUGGAAUUUCAGUGUGCCUGGGCUGUAAAGGUGGCAGUAUGAAUUUUGAAGAUUUUGAAAUGGUUUCUCCAGAUGGGUUUCACCAGGAGAGGAAUCAAAUGAGUCUGCAGAAUCUAGCAGUAAUUGGGAAAAGCAGGAAAGUAUUGUACUGAAAUUGCAAAAGGAAUUUCCCAAUUUUGAUAAACAGGAACUUAGAGAAGUACUCAAGGAACAUGAAUGGAUGUACACAGAAGCUUUAGAAUCUCUAAAAGUGUUUGCAGAAGACCAAGAUAUGCAAUAUGUAUCACAAAGUGAGGUUCCAAAUGGAAAAGAAGUUUCUUCAAGAAGUCAAAAUUACCCUAAAAAUGCAACUAAAACAAAACUAAAACAGAAAUUUUCAAUGAAAGCACAAAAUGGCUUUAACAAGAAACGUAAAAAAAAUGUUUUUAAUCCAAAGAGAGUUGUUGAAGACUCUGAAUAUGAUUCAGGUUCUGAUGUCGGUAGUUCACUAGAUGAGGACUAUAGUAGUGGUGAAGAAGUGAUGGAGGAUGGCUAUAAAGGUAAAAUUCUUCACUUCCUUCAAGAUGCUUCAAUUGGUGAACUUACUUUGAUUCCUCAGUGUUCUCAGAAAAAGGCUCAGAAGAUAACAGAACUCCGGCCCUUUAAUAGUUGGGAGGCUCUGUUCACAAAGAUGUCCAAAACUAAUGGCUUAUCAGAAGAUUUGAUAUGGCACUGUAAAACACUGAUCCAAGAAAGAGAUGUAGUUAUAAGGCUUAUGAACAAAUGUGAAGACAUUUCAAAUAAAUUGACCAAACAAGUUACCAUGCUUACUGGAAAUGGAGGUGGAUGGAACAUAGAACAACCUUCCAUUCUAAACCAAAGUUUGUCACUCAAGCCCUAUCAGAAGGUUGGUUUGAAUUGGCUGGCAUUGGUACAUAAACAUGGACUUAAUGGCAUUUUGGCAGAUGAAAUGGGCCUAGGAAAAACUAUUCAAGCCAUUGCAUUUCUGGCAUACCUCUAUCAGGAGGGUAAUAAUGGUCCUCAUUUGAUCGUUGUUCCAGCUUCAACUAUAGAUAACUGGUUAAGGGAAGUUAAUUUAUGGUGCCCUACUUUGAAGGUCCUCUGUUACUAUGGUUCUCAAGAAGAACGUAAACAAAUUAGAUUUAACAUUCAUAGUAGAUAUGAAGAUUACAAUGUAAUUGUGACCACAUAUAACUGUGCGAUCAGCAGUUCUGAUGACCGUAGUCUGUUUCGACGGCUGAAACUUAAUUACGCAAUUUUUGAUGAGGGCCAUAUGCUGAAGAAUAUGGGCUCCAUUCGCUACCAGCACCUUAUGACAAUUAAUGCAAAUAACCGUUUGCUGCUCACAGGCACACCUGUACAGAACAAUCUGUUAGAACUCAUGUCGCUGUUGAAUUUUGUUAUGCCACACAUGUUUAGUAGUAGCACCAGUGAAAUACGAAGAAUGUUUUCCUCUAAGACAAAAUCAGCAGAUGAGCAAAGCAUAUAUGAAAAGGAGAGAAUAGCACAUGCAAAACAAAUUAUAAAGCCAUUUAUUCUCAGAAGAGUAAAAGAAGAGGUUCUCAAGCAGUUACCCCCCAAGAAAGAUCGAAUUGAGUUGUGUGCAAUGUCGGAGAAGCAGGAGCAACUCUAUUUGGGUCUUUUCAACAGAUUGAAAAAAUCUAUCAAUAACUUGGUCACAGAAAAAAACACAGAAAUGUGCAAUGUCAUGAUGCAGUUGAGGAAAAUGGCCAAUCAUCCUUUAUUACAUCGCCAAUAUUACACAGCUGAAAAACUCAAGGAAAUGUCUCAGCUUAUGCUAAAGGAACCUACACAUUGUGAGGCUAACCCUGACCUGAUCUUUGAAGAUAUGGAAGUUAUGACAGACUUCGAACUACAUGUACUUUGUAAACAGUACCGACACAUUAAUAACUUUCAGUUAGACAUGGACUUGAUUUUAGAUUCUGGAAAAUUUCGAGUUUUAGGAUGCAUCUUGUCUGAAUUGAAACAGAAGGGUGAUAGAGUUGUGUUAUUUAGCCAAUUUACCAUGAUGCUGGAUAUCUUAGAGGUUCUAUUAAAACAUCAUCAGCAUAGGUACCUCAGAUUAGAUGGAAAGACUCAGAUUUCUGAAAGGAUUCAUCUAAUUGAUGAGUUUAAUACCGAUAUGGAUAUCUUUGUGUUUCUGCUAUCAACAAAAGCUGGUGGAUUAGGAAUAAAUCUGACUUCAGCAAAUGUUGUUAUACUUCACGAUAUUGACUGUAAUCCUUAUAAUGACAAACAAGCAGAAGAUAGAUGCCAUAGAGUAGGCCAGACUAAAGAAGUACUAGUUAUAAAACUAAUAAGCCAAGGGACGAUUGAAGAAUCCAUGCUAAAAAUUAACCAACAGAAAUUGAAACUAGAACAGGAUAUGACUACAGUAGAUGAAGGUGAUGAAGGGAGUAUGCCAGCAGAUAUAGCCACAUUACUAAAAACAUCAAUGGGCCUGUGAAAUAAGAACUGUGAACUCUCAAUUGAUGAGGAAAUAUCAACUUGGUGCACUCAAGGACAUUUACAUUAUGAUGACCAUGGGGUUUAUGAACAUUUAUAACUUUUUAUAAUUUCCAUAUUACAUUUCUCAUAGUAUGGACAACUUUUUGCCACUAACUGAAUUCUCCAAAUACUCACACGUGAAAUUUCAAAAAAGAAGCCACAAAUAUGUAGUUCUGAAGAUGUUGAAUAAUCAUUUUACAAAGCAGUUUUCUGAAUGGGGAUUAGUUGGUGAUUGUUUGUAACAAAUAUGCUAAUGCUUUAGAAAUGUCAGUAUUUUUGUAAUUAUUUCUACCUCCAAAUAUAUAUAUAUUGUCUUUCACUGGAUAAUGUGUGUAGAUUUUUACAUGUGCCUUAUUUGACAAUGCUUAUGUCUUGUUUUUGCUUGUCUCAUUUGAAGUUCUUUUUUAUUAUGUUAAAGAAUGCAGCUGUAUAGAUUAUAUAGCUUUCAUUUUAUUGCUAUUUGAAGCAGAUGUUCACCAAUGUCAGCAAGAACUCAACCUGAAUUUAAAGGUGGCAUUCCAUAUACUAACAUCCCCCAGGUCCUCUCAAGUACUUCUGCUGAAACAAAUUUAUUUGGCUAGGCACUAAGUUGUUUUCCAGUGAAUAGUAACUAAAGAAGCCCCUACCUUGCUCCAUGGAUUAAUUCCUUCUGUUCAUUUUCCAACUGCACUAAUUGUGCAUAUUACUCUGCCUAAUCUUGUGCAUGUUUUCAUUGAUUUCCCUCUCCCGGCUUUUGCUUCUCUUGAAACUGUUGCCCAGUCACUUCUGCUCCAAUUCUCUUCCUCUCUAAAUAGUAGUUUAUUACUGCCACAUCUCCAUGCAUCAGCAAAAUGUUGGUGACAUUUUUCUAGCCUGGCAGAACAGAUUACUUAAAGCUAUUUCAUUUCAAAGCAGACUGAAUGUGACUUCAUCUAAAGGCAGCAUUAGGUACUGCAUGGAAAUAGGUCAUUAACUUGAAACUCUUAUCAAAAUAUAUUUUACCAGUUUCCAGAAUUUCCAGUACAGGACCGCCUGAAGAGAGAGCCAUUGUUCAAUUCCAAUUCAGUGUGAGUGACAAAGUGAAAUUUAGAAGUGAAGUUGUCUAUUUGAUAUUUAACUCUUUAUUAAAUCUUUCUUUAAAUUUCUGCCUGUCAGUCUAUAUUGCUGUUUUUAUUAUACAUCAGUUUCUUUGUAUAACUUGUGAGUUCCAUGUGUUUUGUUUUUAUUAUGUAAAUAUCAUUAUAAAUAAACUUAUUUAUAAAUCAAAGAUUUGUUAAUUUUUGGAAAUCAUGCUUUUCAAAGCAUCCUAACUUGCUAAGAUGCUAGGUAGUACGACCCUCUGGAUUUGGAAGGCAAAUAAAACUCUUACAGUGAUUAUUUAGAUAUUAAAGACUGAGAACUCACGGCUUAACCCCAGUCUUGAUGGUAUAUUGAACAGACUGAAUAUAUUUUACCAUUACAGGGCUAAAAGGAGUCUUCAUGUGUUAAUACUACCUCCUUGUACAUCACUAUACCCAAAUCAGUUAUUCAAAUUGUUAGGAAUUUUACCUUUUAAAAUCUCAUAAUGGAUAUCUCAUGUUUUCUGUAUUAAUGUAUUUUCAAUGAUAGGCUGUUUCUUUUUUUGUUGUUAUUGUUGUUGUUGUUAUAUCCAUACUUUUAUCUCUAAUGAAAUGUAGUUGGGUUCUUCCUGUAAUGCGCUAUUAUGUCUUGGGCUUAAUAAAAAUAUUUGUGAUCAUAA